AUGUCCUGCCAGCAGAACCAGCAGCAGUGCCAGCCUCUGCCCAAGUGCCCCUCACCCAAGUGCCCCCCAAAGAGCUCAGCACAGUGUCUGCCUCCAGCCUCCUCCUGCUGUGCUCCAAGACCUGGGUGCUGUGGUGGCCCCAGCUCUGAGGGCGGCUGCUGCCUGAGCCACCACAGGUGCUGCAGGUCCCACCGAUGCCGGCGCCAGAGCUCCAACUCCUGUGACAGAGGCAGUGGUCAGCAAGAUGGUGCCUCCGACUGUGGCUAUGGCUCUGGAGGCUGCUGCUGA